ACCACGUCCCUGGUCCCAGCUCGGGAGCACAUCAGAGGCUUAGAGGCGAGUGGGAAGGGACUCAGACAGUGCAGGACGAGAAACGCCCGCGGCACCAAAGCCCCUCAGAGCGUCGCCCCCGCCUCUAGUUCUAGAAAGUCAGUUUCCCGGCACUGGCACCCCGGAACCUCAGGGGCUGCCGAGCUGGGGGGGCGCUCAAGCUGCGAGGAUCCGGGCUGCCCGCGAGACGAGGAGCGGGCGCCCAGGGGCAACCGCUGUCAUGAGUUACAGUCCUUCCAGGAUGUGCCUCUGAAAAUGGAUUGCAUAUAAAUGAUGGGGUGCAUGAAGUCCAAGUUCCUCCAGGUCGGAGGCAAUACAUUCUCAAAAACUGAAACCAGCGCCAGCCCACACUGUCCUGUGUACGUGCCGGAUCCCACAUCCACCAUCAAGCCGGGGCCUAAUAGCCACAACAGCAACACACCAGGAAUCAGGGAGGCAGGCUCUGAGGACAUCAUCGUGGUUGCCCUGUAUGAUUACGAGGCCAUUCACCACGAAGACCUCAGCUUCCAGAAGGGGGACCAGAUGGUGGUCCUAGAGGAAUCCGGGGAGUGGUGGAAGGCUCGAUCCCUGGCCACCCGGAAGGAGGGCUACAUCCCAAGCAACUAUGUCGCCCGCGUUGACUCUCUGGAGACAGAGGAGUGGUUUUUCAAGGGCAUCAGCCGGAAGGACGCAGAGCGCCAACUGCUGGCUCCCGGCAACAUGCUGGGCUCCUUCAUGAUCCGGGAUAGCGAGACCACUAAAGGAAGCUACUCUUUGUCCGUGCGAGACUACGACCCUCGGCAGGGAGAUACCGUGAAACAUUACAAGAUCCGGACCCUGGACAACGGGGGCUUCUACAUAUCCCCCCGAAGCACCUUCAGCACUCUGCAGGAGCUGGUGGACCACUACAAGAAGGGGAACGACGGGCUCUGCCAGAAACUGUCGGUGCCCUGCAUGUCUUCCAAGCCCCAGAAGCCUUGGGAGAAAGAUGCCUGGGAGAUCCCUCGGGAAUCCCUCAAGCUGGAGAAGAAACUUGGAGCUGGGCAGUUUGGGGAAGUCUGGAUGGCCACCUACAACAAGCACACCAAGGUGGCAGUGAAGACGAUGAAGCCAGGGAGCAUGUCGGUGGAGGCCUUCCUGGCAGAGGCCAACGUGAUGAAAACUCUGCAGCAUGACAAGCUGGUCAAACUUCAUGCGGUGGUCACCAAGGAGCCCAUCUACAUCAUCACGGAGUUCAUGGCCAAAGGAAGCUUGCUGGACUUUCUGAAAAGUGAUGAGGGCAGCAAGCAGCCAUUGCCAAAACUCAUUGACUUCUCAGCCCAGAUUGCAGAAGGCAUGGCCUUCAUCGAGCAGAGGAACUACAUCCACCGAGACCUCCGAGCUGCCAACAUCUUGGUCUCUGCAUCCCUGGUGUGUAAGAUUGCUGACUUUGGCCUGGCCCGGGUCAUUGAGGACAACGAGUACACGGCUCGGGAAGGGGCCAAGUUCCCCAUCAAGUGGACAGCUCCUGAAGCCAUCAACUUUGGCUCCUUCACCAUCAAGUCAGACGUCUGGUCCUUUGGUAUCCUGCUGAUGGAGAUCGUCACCUACGGCCGGAUCCCUUACCCAGGGAUGUCAAACCCUGAAGUGAUCCGAGCUCUGGAGCGUGGAUACCGGAUGCCUCGCCCAGAGAACUGCCCAGAGGAGCUCUACAACAUCAUGAUGCGCUGCUGGAAAAACCGUCCGGAGGAGCGGCCGACCUUCGAAUACAUCCAGAGUGUGCUGGAUGACUUCUACACGGCCACAGAGAGCCAGUACCAACAGCAGCCAUGAUAGGGAGGACCAGGGCAGGGCCAGGGGGUGCCCAGGUGGUGGCUGCAAGGUGGCUCCAGCACCAUCCGCCAGGGCCCACACCCCCUUCCUACUCCCAGACACCCACCCUCGCUUCAGCCACAGUUUCCUCAUCUGUCCAGUGGGUAGGUUGGACUGGAAAAUCUCUUUUUGACUCUUGCAAUCCACAAUCUGACAUUCUCAGGAAGCCCCCAAGUUGAUAUUUCUAUUUCCUGGAAUGGUUGGAUUUUAGUUACAGCUGUGAUUUGGAAGGGAAACUUUCAAAAUAGUGAAAUGAAUAUUUAAAUAAAAGAUAUAAAUGCCAAAGUCUUUACCAAAA